UACGUGAUCAGUACGUGAGUGGCAGGGAUAGUAAAGUCUAUAAUGAGGCCUUCAGAAUAGGGCAAGGCAAUGAUAAGGGUGUAGCCCUUGAUAGCUUACCGAGUGCUUUCAUAUCUAUUAUCUUGUGUACAUAUGUAUAGGGUGGGGGAAAGAUUGGGGGAAAUGAAGAUUGAGAGAAAUCAUUCAGCUCUCCAAAUGGCAGAUCCUGGCUUGAAUCGAGGAAUUCUGAUGCUACAGGUUUACUUAGAGUCAUUGAGAGUUAUAUGCCUUCGGGCCACCUGACAGAGUGAAGCAUACUGCUUUCUGACUAGUAUUAAGACUUGUUAAUGUAGACUGCUUGUCCAAAAACCACCCUGCUGGAACAUGCUAGUUUACCAUGGCAAAGCUCUGUUUUGGGAAUAACGCCUUGCUGGAGACCUUUGAGAUUUGAAAUUUGGAAUGGAAAGGGCUCAAGAGAUUAUUAUUAAAAUAGAAUGGUUUUAGGGAAGACUGUUGCCGGAUGACAAGGCUGUCACUAUUGUUCUGUACUACCUGACAUUAUGGGACCAGGCCAGCCAGCUUCAACCUGUGUUCAUCUAGCACCUAGGACCCAACUUGAUGGGAGGAGCGACCCCAAAGUACUUCAGACCCAGAACCAGCUGCAGUUUAAUAGGAAUGUUCCUACACAUUCAAGCAACUUGGCGAUCCGAUAUUCUUGCCCACAUGCCAUUAGAAUUGAAAAACUGAAGCACUCAUACAAUGAAUCAUACCAUUGUAAAGAUGCAGAUUGUAGAGUUGGUCCUGACCUGGGCAGUUCUGUUUCAUUUUCCGUCAUAUCCCAAGAGAGACUUAGCUAUGCUGUCCACCUAGCCAGAAGAGAUGUGAAACGAAGACAAUUUGAAAAACAUAUAAAAGAACAUCAUCUCAGAAGUCAGCCUCAAAGCUCUCAGAAGUGUGGACAUACUAAGUAUAAAAUACCCGACCACAGGGUGGAAAGGAAGGAAUCAAAGAGUCAAGCAGCCUGUCAGUGUAGCCACCAGCCAUCCAAAGUAGAAAUCUCCAGCUCUGGUGCCAAAGUAUACCUUUACUCAUCUCAUCCAGGCCAGUCAGAUCUUACUGUGCCAAAUUCGCCACCCACCCAUGAUCCGGGACUUCAGCCUCAUCCCAGGAUAGGUGACCACAAAAACAUAAGUGAACAGAAAAGCCUGCUAGAAGUCCAGCGACUCCAGAAAGAACUGAGCAGUUGUAUCCACAAAAUUGAAGAGGUAACUAAAAAAGAUAGACUAGAAGAAGCUUUGGAUCCAGAUGAAGAACGUCGAAUCCGUAUCAGGAGACAGGAGCAAGCUGCUCGCUCUGCCCGAAUGCUCUACGUCCUCCAGCAGCAGGUAAAAGAAAUCCAGGAAGAAUUGGAUAAAUUGAGUCCACAUAAAAUUAAACACACUAAGAAGUCAUGGGCAAUGUCUAAGCUGGCGGCUGCCCAUCGAGGAGCCAUUCGGGCCUUACAGAUGUUUGUCACUCAGUUUACUGACCGAGGGGAGCAUCCACUUCCUGCUCGGUGUAAGGAACUGGGCAGCCUUAUUCGCCAGCUUUCACUUUGUUCUGUCAAGCUGGAUGCAGACCCUUCUGUUCCUGAUGUGGUUAUAGAUAUUCUGCAACAAAUUGAGGCUUUGGAAUCUCUCCUGGAAAAGAAACUGUCACCAAAAAAGGUGAAAAAAUGUUUCAGUGAAAUUCGGAGCAGAUUUCCUAUCGGUAGCCAAAAGGCCUUGGAGAGAUGGCCAAGUACAUCACCAAAGGGUGAGAGGAGGCCCCUCACAGCAAAGGACACAUUCCCACAGGAAACAAGUCGACCUUCUGUAGCAAAGCAGCUUCUUGCCGAUAAGUAUCAGCCCGAUACGGAGCUUCCGGAGACCCAGAGGUUGCAGAGUGAGCUUGAUGUAUUAGAUGCGGAUAUAGUUCUGGAAGAAGGACCAUUUAUUCUAGACCAAAGUGCAAGCUUCAAAGACGAGGUGUUAGCCGUGGCAAAAACAAAAGCAGGGAAAAAGAAGCCUGUGACUGAGAAUGUGCCGUUUAGGAAGAAAGAUACUCUGGCGCCAGCAAGACAGCAAGGACUCCGCAAAGCUGAAAGAGGUAGACAAAGCCAACCUCACAGUAAAAGCAGAGUGCAGCAGACAACAGUUUCAUCCAGAUUAAAAAUGAACCGGCAGCCUGUGAAAGACCGCAAGGCACCAUGGAUACCCCCAAACCCCACAUCCCCACCAGCGUCUCCUAAAUGUGCUGCAUGGCUAAAGGUGAAAACUAGCCCCAGAGAUGCCACAAAAGAGCCUCUCCAGCAAGAAGAUCCUCAAGAGGAAAGUCACCUGACAGGUGCUGUUGAGCAUGAAGCAGCCAGGCUCGCUUGGCUUGAUGCUGAAACUUCCAAAAGAUUGAAGGAACUAGAAGAGUUAAAAGCCAAGGAAAUUGACAGCAUGCAAAAACAGAGGCUUGAUUGGCUUGAUGCUGAAACUUCUAGAAGAACAAAGGAACUGAAUGAGCUCAAAGCUGAAGAAAUGUAUAGACUCCAACAAUUGAGUGUUUCUGCCACCCACUUAGCAGACAAGGUAGAGGAGGCAGUUCUGGAUCGUUUGAAGCCUCUCUUGGUCAAGGCCCAGAGAGUCAAUUCUACUACAGAAGCAAAUAUUCAUUUGAAAGAUGGCUCGUCAGUAAACACAGCGAAAGCCCAGCCUGCACAGGAGGUUUCAGAGCAGAAGGAAAUUGGAAUGAAGCUCCAUUGGCCCAGUGACCUUAGGGGCAGGAAGAAGGUUGCAGCUGUUGAUUUUGAAUCCAACAACAUUCGUCAGCUUGAUGAUUUUUUGGAAGAUUGUGCCAGUGAGCUCUGGGCUGUGACUCAUGCUAAGAUCUUGGGGUCUGAAACCUUAGCCACCGUUGAGGACAGCAAGGAUAGCCCAGAUCUGGAGAUCAUGAUGCGCCGAAUGGAAGAGAUGGAAAAAUACCAGGAGUCUGUUCGUCAAAGAUAUAAUAAAAUCGCAUAUGCUGAUCCUCGACUUUGGAUGCAGGAAGAAAACAAUGACCAAAAAAUCUCAGCAAUAAGUGAAAAGCCUCUAUCUCCUCAUCCAAUCAGAAUCACGAAGACAGUGGAUCGCAAGGAUCCAGCCGUGAACAUCAUGUUAGAAAGGCCCUGUAAUGGCAAUUCCCUGGAUGAAAGUGUGGGAACAGAGGAAGGAUCAGAGAAAAGAGAGGCCCCUCUUCUCUCCCUAGCCGAAGAUUCUCAACAGAAAGAAGGCCGAGCUCCCCUCUUUGUCCCACCGGGUAUGCAGCACAGCAUCGGUGACUACUGUAGUCGUUUUGAGCAGUACCUUCGGAUCAUAUCUCAUGAGGCUGUAGGCUCCUUCAACCCGUGGCUGAUAGCUGAAAGCUUUUCAGAAGAGCUGGUAGAUGAAGCUCUGGGUGCUGUGGCUGCUGAACUUCAGGAUAUGUGCGAAGAUUAUGCAGAAGCUGUGUUCACCUCAGAAUUCUUAGAGGCUGCUACAUAAAGGCUCUCUGAGGCGAGGCCAUUUGUGUCACACUGGAGAAGGGAUGGCACCACCCUUUGUUUUGGCCCACAGGAAAUUUUCAUCCUCAGCUGUCCAUCCAGGCCCAGAAGGUGCUGCCCACUGAAAGGAAGGCAGUGCCGGGGAGGUCAUCCUCACUUUGCAUUUUCUUUUGUCAUGGCAAUGGUUCUGGAAAUGUAUGAUGCAAUGUAUCACACUUAUCAGUGCCCAGGCAACACAACUUGAUUAUGGCAAUAUUUUCAGAAUGUGUACUUUUCCUAUUGAAAUACCAUGUUCAUUCCUCUGGCUCAGUUUGGUGAUGAAAAUGUUUUGAAAGAUAAUCGAUACGUAUAUUUCACACAAGGAUUCAGGUUGCUGUUGAACCCUUGCUGGCAUUGAUACCAACACAAGUGCGGCUACUAGCUGGUCCCAUCACGGGGCCCCUGUUUUGCAUCUUUGGCGAUUUCCUGUCAGGACCUCUGGCCCUACUAGGCUGUAGACUCAGGGAGAGCACAGUCUGGCUGUGCUGCCAAACCUCUCCUCUGCUGCAGUUUAUUCCAAACAGGAGCCCCCUGGCUGUCAGUGCACAAUAAUAGACACACAUUUCUUCAACGUUCCAUUCCUAGGUGAUUUUCACAUUUUUAGUUCCUCAGCAUAUUUUAUUGCUGUGUGUUGACACAAUCUGGUAUAAAAAACUUUCUCUGGAUUCAGAGGAAGUUUGAGGAAUCAGGAGAGGACCAGGCCUUCUCCUGUGCCUGGGUGAAGGUACAGACCUCGCUGUGUCUCCGAUGAGGUCAGAAGUGUCUCUAUUUCAUACCACAAAGGAACCCAAGUGGGAGUAGGGAACAGAUGGAUGGCGCGAAGACCUCUGUGUCUCCCCAGAGAAAGGAAGAAACUUAAGAACCAUCAUAGCCUGGUCCUCCAACAUCUUACAGAUCAUGUUUUCCAAGAGAAAAGCCUGUGUUUUCAGAAACUCUGAAUUCAGAAAAAGAAACGGAAUGUGCGUAAGAAUCAGGCCACUGCCUGGAAAGACUUUCUCUCAAUUCGUAGCCUGAGGCUCAGUGAAGGAAACAUGCAGAAAGAAUGCCUGAGACGCCCCCAGGGAAUAAGGGAACUCUUUAUAACCUGUCCAGUGCCGUCAUCUGGGAUUUUUCUCUGAAGUACAAGAAUUUCAGGUGAUUUAAGCUGCUUGAUCACACUUAUUUGUGCAAAAUUGAUUUUCAUUUAAUGUUAAUGUUUUCCUGCUUAAUUUUAUAUAACUUCAGAAUGUAAAGAGCUUCAAGGUAAAUUACAGGGUGUUUAACCUGGGGAGUUAAAUGUGUACACUUGAAUUAAUAGGAGCACCGGUUGUUGCUAGUAUAAAGUAAUUUGUGUGGCAGUUUGUACUGUGCUGAGUUUUUAAAAUAAACCCAAUAUUUUAAAGUAUGUGCCUAUUUUAAAUAACUUACAUCUCCUUUUUUUCCCACAGGCAAAGUGAAAUGUGAUUUACAGAAACCACUGAGAAUACUUUUAUAUGUGAUAUGACUAUAGUGGAUUAUUUGCCACCCCUUCCCCCCGAGAAAAAAAUUAGUGACAAUAAAAGCUAACAUUUAUUGAGCACCUA